GACUCAGUCUCUGAGCGUUUUAAUACGAUGGUGUCCCCGCGGGAUCAAACUUCAGCGUCACAGCUGAGGACUGGCUUCGUGGUCCCUGAUGGGAGAGCAUGAACAGGUGGUAUGUGCCUCCCAGGCUUCCUAUGGUCCCUAAGUCCCGGGUUCUCAGCGUGACAUUCCAGAGCAAACACAGCUCCCCAUUACUCUAUACCAGGCACUGGCAUGGAUUAAUUUAUCUAAUCACAACAUCCCAGUAAGCGACCCUCUUUUGGCCGGCCUACCCCGGGACCCUGACUACUCUGUGUCCUGCCUCUACUCACCUCCCUCACCCUCCAGCAUGUGUUUGCCUGCUAACAUGAAGUGUGACAAGUACUGGGGCUCUUCCUCGGACAAGGCUCUGGAGCGUACAGCUCACUGGUCCAGGACUCCAGAGCCAGAGACCUUGGGAUGCCCUGCUUCUGGGGACACAGUGAGGACUGCAGACUGCAGGCCAGGAAGCCCUUGGAGACCAGCUCUUCCAAAGUCAAAGCCAAGACCAUUGUGAUGAUUCCCGACUCCCAGAAGCUCCUGCGAUGUGAACUUGAGUCACUCAAGAGCCAGUUACAGGCCCAGACCAAGGCUUUCGAGUUCCUGAACCACUCAGUGACCAUGUUGGAGAAGGAGAGCUGCUUGCAGCAAAUCAAGAUUCAGCAGCUUGAAGAGGUGCUGAGCCCCACAGGCCGCCAGGGAGAGAAGGAGGAGCACAAGUGGGGCAUGGAGCAGGGCCGGCAGGAGCUGUAUGGGGCCCUGACCCAAGGCCUUCAGGGGCUGGAGAAGACCCUGCGUGACAGUGAGGAGAUGCAGCGGGCCCGCACCACUCGCUGCCUGCAGCUGCUGGCCCAGGAGAUCCGGGACAGCAAGAAGUUCCUGUGGGAGGAGCUGGAACUGGUGCGGGAGGAGGUGACCUUCAUCUAUCAGAAGCUCCAAGCGCAGGAGGAUGAGAUCUCAGAGAACUUGGUGAACAUUCAGAAAAUGCAGAAAACGCAGGUGAAAUGCCGCAAAAUCCUGACCAAGAUGAAGCAGCAGGGUCAUGAGACAGCCGCCUGUCCGGAGACUGAAGAGAUACCGCAGGGAGCCAGUGGCUGCUGGAAGGAUGACCUCCAGAAGGAACUGAGUGAUAUAUGGUCUGCUGUGCACGUGCUGCAGAACUCCAUAGACAGCCUCACUUUGUGCUCGGGGGCCUGUCCCAAGGCCUCGAGCCUAAGAGGCCACAAGGGGCACCAGUGCCUGAGCCCUCCACUCCCCUCCUGGGACUCUGACUCCGACUGUGACCAGGACCUCUCCCAGCCACCUUUCAGCAAGAGCGGCCGCUCCUUCCCACCCGGUGCAGAUCCUCCCCAGUCCCCCCCUCCACCCAUUUCCCUCCUGACCUGCCCUUGACUCCCACAGUCUAGACCCUCAGAACAGGCCCAGAUCCUGAUCUGGGCAUGCGGUCCCUGACCUGCAGCCCCGGAGUCCCCUGGACCUGGCCAGGCCCUGACCCACCCUCUCUCUCCACAGCUUGAGCAGCCGGGACUGCUCUCCCUGAAGACCCCUCCAGAGAGAAAAUAAACUAGCCCAGACCCUCCUCUA